GGUCUGCAUCUCCAUCGGAAAGUGCGCUUGCCACAUCCCUUCGGAUCACUUCGUCCUCCCGAGAGCGUUCUGCCUUCUACAGCUCGGAAAGAAAGAAAUCUUAGCUGUGAAGUGACCGUGGAGAAAGCGCAGGAAGCGACACAAUUGGUUAGGGAGGCAGAGAGUGUGAGCGGGCGCACCCCUUGCCUGGGGACCGCGCUCGCGGGCGGGGACGGAGCAUCCCAGUGGCUGCACCCGCCGCUCCGCGCUCCUGCCUGGCGUCGCCAACCCCGCGGCGGCCGCUGGAAUUCCAGAGCUGCCAGGCGCUCCCAGCCGGUCUCGGCAAACUUUUCCCCAGCCCACGUGCUAACCAAGCGGCUCGCUUCCCGAGCCCGGGAUGGAGCACCGCGCCUAGGGAGGCCGCGCCGCCCGAGACGUGCGCACGGUAGGCAACCCACACCAAGGCAGCCGCAGCUGCGGCGCUUGGGUACACCGCCGUGGACUCCAAAUGGCCUAAGAGCGUUCUUUUAGCCCUGCGCUCUCAGUGCCUUUAGAGUUCUUUCCUUUCCCCGGAGCGCCGGCACAACGCAUUAUGCCGCUGGGUCGGAGCUUAGGGCUCGGCAGAGGUUGCUAAUUCACUGAUUAUAAUCACCUUCCUCUCCAACUCGUCCGCAGCUGCCCGCUCUGGAUUAAGCCGCUCCGCGGCUCGUGCUAGGCAGUUCGUGGCGGAGAGAUGCUGAUCGCGCUGAACUGACCGGUGCGGCCCGGGGGUGAGUGGCGAGUCUCCCUCUGAGUCCUCCCCAGCAGCGCGGCCGGCGCCGGCUCUUUGGGCGAACCCUCCAGUUCCUAGACUUUGAGAGGCGUCUCUCCCCCGCCCGACCGCCCAGAUGCAGUUUCGCCUUUUCUCCUUUGCCCUCAUCAUUCUGAACUGCAUGGAUUACAGCCACUGCCAAGGCAACCGAUGGAGACGCAGUAAGCGAGGAUGCAGAAUAGAAAACUGUGAUUCUUGCUUUAGCAAAGACUUUUGUACCAAGUGCAAAGUAGGCUUUUAUUUGCAUAGAGGCCGUUGCUUUGAUGAAUGUCCAGAUGGUUUUGCACCAUUAGAAGAAACCAUGGAAUGUGUGGGAUGUGAAGUUGGUCAUUGGAGCGAAUGGGGAACUUGUAGCAGAAAUAAUCGCACAUGUGGAUUUAAAUGGGGUCUGGAAACCAGAACACGGCAAAUUGUUAAAAAGCCAGUGAAAGACACAAUACUGUGUCCAACCAUUGCUGAAUCCAGGAGAUGCAAGAUGACAAUGAGGCAUUGUCCAGGAGGGAAGAGAACACCAAAGGCGAAGGAGAAGAGGAACAAGAAAAAGAAAAGGAAGCUGAUAGAAAGGGCCCAGGAGCAACACAGCGUCUUCCUAGCUACAGACAGAGCUAACCAAUAAAACAAGAGAUCCGGUAGAUUUUUAGGGGUUUUUGUUUUUGCAAAUGUGCACAAAGCUACUCUCCACUCCUGCACACUGGUGUGCAGCCUUUGUGCUGCUCUGCCCAGUAUCUGUUCCCAGUAACAUGGUGAAAGGAAGCACCACCAGCAUGGCCCCUGUGUUAUUUAUGCUUUGAUUUGAAUCUGGAGACUGUGAAGGCAGGAGUAAGUGCACAGCCCGUGACUUGGCUCAGUGUGUGCUGAGAGAAUCCGUCCCCGGCACCAUGGACAUGCUAGAGGUGUGAGGCUGCAGAACACCGCUGGAGGACGGACUUGUGCCUAUUUAUGUGAAAGAAGAUGCUUGGCAGGCAAUGCGCUACUCACUCGUGACCUUUAUUUCUCACAUUGUGCAUUUUCAAGGAUAUGUUUGUGUGGAUAUCUGCUUAGUGUUACCACAUGGUAUUCUCAGCAUGUUACCUUCACACUGUUGUGCGAUGAAACUGCUUUUAGCUGAGGAUAUGCUCUGGAAAUUCCUGCUCAGUUUCACUGCAGCCCUAAUAUGUACAUAUACUGCAGGAGCUACAUAUAAAGCUCUUAUUUACUGUAUAUUUAUGCUUUCUUGUGGGUAACAAGUCAUACCUGAUUAAUAUGAUGCCACUUUGUUUCUAGUGGUUCCUAACCCAUUGUCUGAUAAAUGACUUUUCUAGUUUGGGGAAUUGACACUUGUUUUGUUGCCUCUUGAAACUUUUUUUUUUUCCCCUCAUUGUGGGCUUAUUUCUCAUUGUAAGGGUAGGAUAAACUAGUUUUUGUAUAUAGAGUCAAAUGACCAGUGUCAAAGAGUUUGCAUAUUGGGUAGACCUUCUCCACUCCACAUGUCCCACACAUAUAGAUAAAGCAGCAGGCGGCAUCUGGCAAUCAGAAGCCCAAACUGCCUUUGAGUCUAAGAUGUGAUGACUUUGAUGAAACACAACUGAAAACAUGAGGGACUAUAUCCAGUCACUUGUAGCCAGUUUCACAGGCCAGCUACAGAAUUGUCCAAACAAACAUUAUUUCUGACUGCAAUUUUUUUCCCCCAAAUUUAAAGCAAUCCCUGGCUUUAAAUGACAAGGCACCUACCAAUGUUCUUGGGUCACUGAAGAAGCUACUACCAUGAGCCUGGGCAUAGAAUUUUAGGAGAUAAAAGGAUGAAUUUCUGUGACUGCCAGUCAGAUCUUAACAGGUUUCUGUUGAGCCAGAAUCUGUUUCAGAUCCAAGAUGGAGAGGAACACUAUGGAAACUUCCCAGGUGACUUUCAGAGCAGUUGUUUCAAACACAUCAUUGUCCUUUUAGGGGAACCAGUUUUUAGAAGGUUGUGAAUUGGCUUUUUCACAAAGCAUGAUUAUCUUCCUGGCUGAUCCAGGAGAAAAUUAGAACAGAAAAAUAAUGGUUGUGGAUUUUGAAACAAAGCAAGGUAAAGCCUUUUUUUUUUCACCUUGCAUUGGCAAAACUACCUCUUCAGUGUUUUUAACUUUUGAUUCAAAAGCAUCUUACCAAUAAGGAUAAAUAUCAUAUACAUCGUUAUGAAAAUAUUGCUAUGAGAUAAUAAGCCACAUAUGAAUGUUGUAUACAACUUUAGGGUUUACAUUUAAUCCUGAAGUGUUACCUCCUUUCAUGUCUAUUUACACUAUUUUCCCAUUUACUAAGUGGGGAGGGGGUCUCCUUAUAUAGUGCUUCAUCGUUAAUAAGUCAAUACCUGUUGUUCCUGGGAUGUUCUUUUUUGUGCAUUAAAAACUUCAAAAUUA